CAGACUCGCAGGGCAAUGACAUUAAAGUCACUGCUGAGAGCACUGGUGAACAUGCCUCCUCACUACCGCUACCUUUGCAUCAGCCACCUCAUUGGAUGGACAGCCUUCCUGUCCAACAUGCUGUUCUUCACAGAUUUCAUGGGCCAGAUUGUGUACCGCGGGGAUCCCUAUAGUGCACACAACUCCACAGAGUUUCUCAUCUACGAAAGAGGAGUCGAGGUUGGAUGUUGGGGCUUGUGCAUCAACUCCGUGUUUUCCUCACUUUAUUCUUACUUUCAGAAAGUUUUGGUAUCCUACAUUGGAUUAAAGGGUCUUUACUUCACGGGAUAUUUGCUGUUUGGCCUGGGGACGGGAUUUAUUGGGCUCUUCCCGAAUGUCUACUCCACCCUGGUCCUGUGCAGCCUGUUUGGUGUAAUGUCCAGCACCCUGUACACUGUGCCCUUUAACCUCAUUACUGAGUACCACCGCGAGGAAGAAAAGGAGGUGUGCUGUCAUUGAACCUCUGCCUUGGGUAACAUCCAGACUCAUCUGAAGGCUGGGGAGGAUUUGGUAGCAAUGUGUAGAGCAGAGCUGGAAAAUAAGGGUUCUUGAAACAGCAACAGUCAAAUGCCCAACCAACUGCAACCAUGAUCUGGUACAGGCAUGCUCACCAGCCCAGCCCAGCCCAGCUGUCCUGUCCUCCUUAUUCUCAACUCCUGCUCACUUAGGGAGCUGUAGGGCAAGAAGUGUUACUCCCAUUUUUCUAAUUAGAAAAAGGCUUGGUGAGGCUGAGAAACCAGCCCACAAUUACACAAAGACAAAAAAAGGGGGACCCAGGUCUUCUGUAACCACCUCAUAGGUCUCCCUGGUGCCACCUGCAGCAUUUCUAGAUACCGACAAUAAGGGUCUCCCUAUCCCCAACUUUCAGAGGUACAUAGUGGAAUUUCUUGGCAUUAUUUGCUGAGGGUAGGAAAGUCCUAGGCAAUGGAGUCCAGAUUUUAGUAAGUCAGACCCCAUGUGUGAGAAGGAAAGCUGGAAUCAUGGGUGGUAAUCCCCACUUUGCUGCCCUGAGCGGGACCUGUGCCAUUUAAACCUUGGAACGCAACUAGUGAACAAGCGCCUAUGCAGUGCUUAUAACAGAGUUGGUGUUUCCACUCUAAAAUUACCACCUCUUCUUAUCAAAAUUUGCAACUUUCUUCCUGUGAAAAUAGGCUUAUAGUUCCUUAACUGGAGCAAUGAUAUAAAAGCUACAGAGAUAACUCCAAGUUUAAUCCAGCUCAGCAUGAAACUGCAAAAACACUGAACAUAUAACCAUCAGACUAUAAUUCUGGCCAUGUUUUUCAUCAUUUGAUCUGGCAGCAGGGCAGAGGUGCACCAGGAGUAAAAACCUUUCAAAAAAGAGGUGUGGCUUUCCUCAUCCCCUGGCAAACAUUGUCACCAAGGUGGGAUGUUGCUGCUAAUGGGAGAGUCAUCAUAAAAAACUGUCCCUACAAGGAGAGUGUUACAUGGUGUUGGGGGAAGAAAACCUACGCUUCAGGCUCAGAGAAACCUGGAUUCAAAUCCUGCCUCUCUCACUUGGAAGCUGUGUUACACUGGGGAUGUUAUUUACUUGUUUAUUAGUUAGCACUUAGAAUGAGUUCAUUUUUAGGUGAGAUAAUAUAUUCACAAUGAUACACAAAAGUGCACACUGUGUGCUCCCUUUACCAUUUACUAUCUCCCUCCAGCCCCAACGUGUUACCACUCUUACUAGUUUUUUGUUAAUCUUUCCGGCAUUUUUAAAUAAAAACCAAGCAAAUGUAAA